ACACCAGGUCUUGGAGCAAGAGAACUUGGCAGGCUCUCCCCAUGGCAGUCUUAUUCCUCCUCCUGUUCCUAUGUGGAACUCCCCAGGCUGCAGACAACAUGCAGGCCAUCUAUGUGGCCUUGGGGGAGGCAGUAGAGCUGCCAUGUCCCUCACCACCUACUCUACAUGGGGACGAACACCUGUCAUGGUUCUGCAGCCCUGCAGCAGGCUCCUUCACCACCCUGGUAGCCCAAGUCCAAGUGGGCAGGCCAGCCCCAGACCCUGGAAAACCAGGAAGGGAAUCCAGGCUCAGACUGCUGGGGAACUAUUCUUUGUGGUUGGAGGGAUCCAAAGAGGAAGAUGCCGGGCGGUACUGGUGCGCUGUGCUAGGUCAGCACCACAACUACCAGAACUGGAGGGUGUACGACGUCUUGGUGCUCAAAGGAUCCCAGUUAUCUGCAAGGGCUGCAGAUGGAUCCCCCUGCAAUGUCCUCCUGUGCUCUGUGGUCCCCAGCAGACGCAUGGACUCUGUGACCUGGCAGGAAGGGAAGGGUCCCGUGAGGGGCCGUGUUCAGUCCUUCUGGGGCAGUGAGGCUGCCCUGCUCUUGGUGUGUCCUGGGGAGGGGCUUUCUGAGCCCAGGAGCCGAAGACCAAGAAUCAUCCGCUGCCUCAUGACUCACAACAAAGGGGUCAGCUUUAGCCUGGCAGCCUCCAUCGAUGCUUCUCCUGCCCUCUGUGCCCCUUCCACGGGCUGGGACAUGCCUUGGAUUCUGAUGCUGCUGCUCACAAUGGGCCAGGGAGUUGUCAUCCUGGCCCUCAGCAUCGUGCUCUGGAGGCAGAGGGUCCGUGGGGCUCCAGGCAGAGAUGCCUCGAUUCCUCAGUUCAAACCCGAAAUCCAGGUCUAUGAGAACAUCCAUUUGGCCCGUCUUGGCCCACCUGCCCACAAGCCCAGGUGAUUUUGGUGACAUCUGCUGGGAAGUGUGACCUGCUGUCUCGCUGGCCAUCUGGCACCUGGAAGAUUCCUCGACAACCUUAGCAAGGGGG